CUUUCGAUUGUAGCAUUUCUCCUUUCAGGAUACAGUACGGGAUCCUUUCUGGAAUGGAGGUCUUAUGAGCUGCUAUUGAACACGGCAGAGCCUGUUGGUGACCUGCACACAGGAGCCCUCCAGUCAGUACUGAUUGAAUUACUCAAGGCUGCCUCUCUGCAAAGUUGAGCACUACAGGACGUCGGGACUGGGCAUUUCCUUCCAACAUGGCCGCCACUGCCUCUCCGCAGCCACUCGCCACUGAGGAUGCCGAUUCUGAGAAUAGCAGCUUCUAUUACUAUGACUACCUGGAUGAAGUGGCCUUCAUGCUCUGCAGGAAGGAUGCAGUGGUGUCCUUUGGCAAAGUCUUCCUCCCAGUCUUCUAUAGCCUGAUUUUUGUGUUGGGCCUCAGCGGGAACCUCCUUCUUCUCAUGGUCUUGCUCCGUUACGUGCCUCGCAGGCGGAUGGUUGAGAUCUAUCUGCUGAAUCUGGCCAUCUCCAACCUUCUGUUUCUGGUGACACUGCCCUUCUGGGGCAUCUCCGUGGCCUGGCAUUGGGUCUUCGGGAGUUUCUUGUGCAAGAUGGUGAGCACUCUUUAUACUAUUAACUUUUACAGUGGCAUCUUUUUCAUUAGCUGCAUGAGCCUGGACAAGUACCUGGAGAUCGUUCAUGCUCAGCCCUACCACAGGCUGAGGACCCGGGCCAAGAGCCUGCUCCUUGCUACCAUAGUAUGGGCUGUGUCCCUGGCCGUCUCCAUCCCUGAUAUGGUCUUUGUACAGACACAUGAAAAUCCCAAGGGUGUGUGGAACUGCCACGCAGAUUUCGGCGGGCAUGGGACCAUUUGGAAGCUCUUCCUCCGCUUCCAGCAGAACCUCCUAGGGUUUCUCCUUCCACUCCUUGCCAUGAUCUUCUUCUACUCCCGUAUUGGUUGUGUCUUGGUGAGGCUGAGGCCCGCAGGCCAGGGCCGGGCUUUAAAAAUAGCUGCAGCCUUGGUGGUGGCCUUCUUCGUGCUAUGGUUCCCAUACAAUCUCACCUUGUUUCUGCAUACGCUGUUGGACCUGCAAGUAUUCGGGAACUGUGAGGUCAGCCAGCAUCUAGACUACGCACUCCAGGUAACAGAGAGCAUCGCCUUCCUUCACUGCUGCUUUUCCCCCAUCCUGUAUGCCUUCUCCAGUCACCGCUUCCGCCAGUACCUGAAGGCUUUCCUGGCUGCCGUGCUUGGAUGGCACCUGGCACCUGGCACUGCCCAGGCCUCAUUAUCCAGCUGUUCUGAGAGCAGCAUACUUACUGCCCAAGAGGAAAUGACUGGCAUGAAUGACCUUGGAGAGAGGCAGUCUGAGAACUACCCUAACAAGGAGGAUGUGGGGAAUAAAUCAGCCUGAGUGACCAAAUUUUGGUCUGGUGGGAACAGAUGGGAACCAGCUCAAUUGGGUGUCCACUCAAAGUGCUCUCUCCAGGGGCCUCAGUGACUGUGUUGCUAAACCCAGUGGUCAGUUCUCAGUUCUCAGCCAUCAGCAGCAUUUGCUCGCCCCGCCUUCUUCCUCCACUUUCUUCACUUGCUUCCAGGAUACCACGCUUUCUUUUCUGAAUUGCUACAAUCUUUCUUCCUUCCUUCCUUGCUUCCUUCCUUCCUUCCUUCCCUCUCUCCCUCCCUCCCUCCCUCGCUUCUUCCCUUCCUCCUUUCCUCCCUUCCUACUUUCCUUCCUUCCUUCUGACAGGGUCUUGCUCUAUUGCUCUGUCACCCAGGCUGGAAUGCAGUGGCGAGAUCUCCGCUCACUGUAGCCUCCUCCCCCUGGGUUGAAGCAAUUCUCAUGCCUCAGCCUCCCAAGUAGCCAGGACUAUAGGCACCUGCCACCAUGCCUGGCUAAUUUUUGUAUUUUUUUUCUUUCUUUCUUUCUUUUCUUUUUUUUUUUUUUUUGAGACGGAGUCUCACUCUUGUUGCCCAGGCUGGACAACAAUGGCGCGAUCUCGGCUCACUGCAACCUCCACCUCCCGGAUUCAAGCGAUUCUCCUGCCUCAGCCUCCUGAGUAGCUGGAACUACAUGCGCGUGCCACCACGCACAGCUAAUUUUUAUAAUUUUAGUAGAGAUGGGGUUUCACUGCGUUGGCCAGGAUGAUCUCGAUCUCUUGACCUUGGGAUCCACCCGCCUUGGCCUCCCAAAGUGCUGGGAUUACAGGUGUGAGCCACCAUGCCUGGCCCUAAUUUUUGUGUUUUUAUUAGAAACAGAGUUUCACCAUGUUGGCCAGGCUGGAGAAUUGCUGUAAUAGUUUUCCAACUGGCCCCUGUCCUUCCUCUCUCUUGCUCUCCUCCCAUCUCAUCUGCACCUAGCAGCCAGAGUGAUCCUGAUACUCUCGGCCUUUACUUCCGCCUCCCUCAGAGCAGCAGCCUGUCAAAACACCAGAUUACAACAAAUUUAGUUUAAAGGUCUCAAUUAGCGUUAUUGGCAAUUCUAGAAUCAGGCAACAGACUCAUUGAAUCAGGAACAGAUUCACUCCAUAAAAUACAGAGAGUGCUGCAAUGAGCUGGGUAGAAGAGGUUAGUUUUAUAGACAGGAAGGGGCUGUCAAAGGCAGAAAGAAAUGAAGAACAAAAAAAAAGAUUGAUUUUUUUUUUUUUGAGACAGGAUCUCACUCUGUCAUCCAGGCUGAAGUCCAAUCCCACAAUCAUGGCUCACUGCAGCCACCACCUCCUGAGCUCAAGUGAUCCUCCCAUCUAAGCCCCCAAGUAGCUAGGACUACAGGAGCACACCACCACACCUGGCUAAUUUUUGUAUUUUUUGUGGAGACAGGGUCUCAGUAUGUUACCCAGGUUGGACUGGAAACCCUUGGCUCAAGCAAUUUGCCUGCCUCAGCCUCCCAAAGUGCUGGGAUUACAGGCGUGAGCCACUGCACAGGGCCAGAUUCAUCAUUUCAAAGUUACUUUCUAUAUGCGGCCGGAACAGGGUGGUUGACAUCAGUUUUCUUCAGGUUACUUUUUAAUAAUGAUUAAAACGGGGAACUUCAUUAUCAUGA